GUCCCUGGCGGCGGAGAUGGCGGCGACAGCGGCGGAGGCUGUGGCCUCUGGCUCUGGAGAGCCCCGGGAGGAGGCUGGAGCCCUCGGCCCCGCCUGGGAUGAAUCCCAGUUGCGCAGUUAUAGCUUCCCGACUAGGCCCAUUCCGCGUCUGAGUCAGAGCGACCCCCGGGCAGAGGAGCUUAUUGAGAAUGAGGUGGGGGGCGGGGCCGCGUCUAAAGGGAGAGGAGGAAGGUACCCGGUUGAGAGGUCAGAGGAGCCUGUGGUGCUGACCGACACAAAUCUUGUGUAUCCUGCCCUGAAAUGGGACCUUGAAUACCUGCAAGAGAAUAUUGGCAAUGGAGACUUCUCUGUGUACAGUGCCAGCACCCACAAGUUCUUGUACUAUGAUGAGAAGAAGAUGGCCAAUUUCCAGAACUUUAAGCCGAGGUCCAACAGGGAAGAAAUGAAAUUUCAUGAGUUCGUUGAGAAACUGCAGGAUAUACAGCAGCGAGGAGGGGAAGAGAGGUUGUAUCUGCAGCAAACGCUCAAUGACACUGUGGGCAGGAAGAUUGUCAUGGACUUCUUAGGUUUUAACUGGAACUGGAUUAAUAAGCAACAGGGAAAGCGUGGCUGGGGGCAGCUUACCUCUAACCUGCUGCUCAUUGGCAUGGAAGGAAAUGUGACACCUGCUCACUAUGAUGAGCAGCAGAACUUUUUUGCUCAGAUAAAAGGUUACAAACGAUGCAUCUUAUUCCCUCCGGAUCAGUUCGAGUGCCUCUACCCAUACCCUGUUCAUCACCCAUGUGACAGACAGAGCCAGGUGGACUUUGACAAUCCCGACUACGAGAGGUUCCCUAAUUUCCAAAAUGUGGUUGGUUACGAAACAGUGGUUGGCCCUGGUGAUGUUCUUUACAUCCCAAUGUACUGGUGGCAUCACAUAGAGUCAUUACUAAAUGGGGGGAUUACCAUCACUGUGAACUUCUGGUAUAAGGGGGCUCCCACCCCUAAGAGAAUUGAAUAUCCUCUCAAAGCUCAUCAGAAAGUGGCCAUAAUGAGAAACAUUGAGAAGAUGCUUGGAGAGGCCUUGGGGAACCCACAAGAGGUGGGGCCCUUGUUGAACACAAUGAUCAAGGGCCGAUACAACUAGCCUGCCAGGGGUCAAGGCCUCCUGCCAGGUGACUGCUAUCCCGUCCACACCGCUUCAUUGAUGAGGACAGGAGACUCCAAGCGCUAGUAUUGCACGCUGCACUUAAUGGACUGGACUCUUGCCAUGGCCCAGGAGUCAGGUGUUUGGAGCGAGGCAGGGCAGUUGGCACUCCACUCCUAUUUGGAGGGACUUCAUACCCUUGCCUCUUGUGCCCCAGCACCUUCUCUCUCUGCCCCCCGCCUAAAGUCCUGCAUUCAGUGUGUGGAGUCCCAGCUUUUGGUUGUCAUCAUGUCUGUGUGUAUGUUAGUCUGUCAACUUCGGAAUGUGUGCGUGUGUGUGCAUGCACACGCAUGUAUGUAUCUGUUCCCUGUUCCUUCUGGGUCAGGCUGUCACUUCCGGCUCUCAGCCCUAUCUCCUGCAACCUCAGUGCCUCAGCCUGAGAGAGAGAUGAGAUGCUCUUGGACUCCCCACUGCAUCUGGGCUGCAGGGCCAGAGCUAGUCUGACCAUUAGGUCAGUCUGCCUCCUGACAGUUUUUGCGUAGUCAAGCUCUAGGCGGUAUGGGAAUGGCUACCGGGACUCUAAUGGGGUGAAAGAGAGGGGAGGCUUGCCUUUGAGAGCCUAUAUAGCCUUCCUGUGAGAGAGGAUUAGAUAGGGUUCCAACUGGGCCUACAAGCUCAAGCCAUACAUAAAAGGACCUUGGGACAUAAGAACCAAUGAUUGUGCAUAAGUUCUAAAUUAGAGACACAUAUAGUUUCUCUCUUUCAGCACCAGCUCUUGCCCCUAUGCUGGGUACCAAGGGAGUUCUCCUAGCUGUGGCUUCUCUAGGUUCUAGGGGUGCAAGCCUCUGUGUGUUUGUUUGUGUGUGUCUGUGUGUGCGUAUCCACACUAGGGGUGCAAGCCUCUGGGUGUGUGUGUGUGUGUGCGUGCGUGUGUGUGUGUGUGUCCGUGUGUGUGUGUGUGUGUGUCCACACUGGCCAGCCUCCCUACUUACCAAGGUUCUCCACUGCUUACCUUUUCCAGUGGGACAGUACAGUGUGAGCCCCCGGGAAGUACUGCCUGACCUAUCCUAAGCUUUUACACUUGGAUUUUAGCCAUCAUAUGUUGGCCAGGUCUCACUGCAGCCUGCCCGAGGCUAACUGGCUAGAGCCUCCAGGCCCUAUGAUGCUCCCUGCCCAGGCCAUAUCCUUUAUUCCUGCUGAGCUUCCUGGCUGAAUAGAUGAAAUGGGGUCAAGCCCAGGCAGCUCAUUCACUACCUGUGAUCCACCUCAGGGCACGGGCAAACACAUAGGCUUGCGUCUUAAAGCCAGCUCCUCUGCCAGACCCCGUUGUAAUGUGCCACAACACCCUCAAUAGUCAGGGCAACUGGUGGAGCAUGGAAGUCGAAUUUCCUUUUCUGUUAGGAGCUACUCCUGGGAACCCCUCUCAGGGCUGCAGCUUACAGGUGGGCAGCUGUGAUUGCACAACUUGAAGGGCCAUCAUUCACAUCUAUUCAGUGGGAGUGGGGUCCCUGGGAUUGGGCAGUGUGGUGGCCCUGUGUCUCCUCACCUCUGCUCCUGUCUUCAUCACCUUCUCUCUGGAAGGGAAGAGGAGUUGGAAGGUCUCUGGUUUUCUUUUCUUUUUUUUUUUUUUUGCCAAAGGUUUACUUCCAGCAUCUGAGCUCUGGCUCUCACCCCUGAAGCUCAGUUAUAGUGCACUGAUGAACUGAGAGGAUGCGUGUGGAUGUGUGUGCAUGCCUGAGUGCGUUUUUUGGGGAGGGGUGUUUAUUUUUAGUACCCCAUUCUGGGGUUCUCUGAUGCAGUGUGGAUGUGAAGAUAUGGUACCUUCUCAAGUGUAGCUCUUUCAAAUAUAGUCAAUGCUGGGAAAUGUGAUUGCAGUGAUCUCUAUCUCUCCACUUCUUUUGGGAAAGAGGAGCACAGGAGCGGAGGAAAAACUUGGCCACAGUCACACUUGGAAAGAUAGUAGAUUAUUUUCGUUCUCCUCAGCAGGUCUGCUGUAUUCCUCGCUCAGCGCUCAAAGAUGUGGGUGAUGUGUCAAGGAGGCAUGCACUCAGCUGGUCCUUGCUGAGUUAUUUGCUGACACAGGUCUCACUAAGGUGGCUGAGGGGUGGGAGGGAGAAGGCUAAUCUUGGAACCUUCACAGGAUUGGCCUUGAUCCUUGGGUAACACAAGAGUGAUUCCUGAUUUUUAGACACCUAAUAUGUGCCUAGUGCUUUUCUCUUUGUUCCUCACUAUCCUGCAAGGUAGGUAUUCUCACUUACAGAUGAAUAAAUGGGCUCAGAGAGAUUAGGUGAUUAGUGACAAUCAGUUGUAACUUAGCACUGUUAGGCUGCAAACCCCUUGCUCCUUCCUUUCCACCAAACUAUGUUGAUUUUCCUUCCUUACCUCCCUCCUUGUACCACAGGUUCUGUCCUCAAGAUAUCACCCCACUGGGCAGUAUCUGAAGGCAGACCCAGCCCAAGAUGGUGCAGAAUAUACAGCUCAGGGUGAAAGUUCUUCUGGGCUCCUGCUAACAAAGUCUUGGAAAAACUGCCUGGGAAGCCAUAUUAUGAAUUAGUGCUAGAAGAAGCUGUGGGGGGAACUGAGUUCUGUGUCUAAUUGCAUUACUUAUGUGUCCUUGAAUAGGACCCAUAACUCCUCCCGGCAUGCUUUUGCAUCUAUAGAACUGAAGCUGUAGUUCUAGAUGGCACUAAGGGUCUUGGUUCAUAUUCAGCUGCUGCUUCCCCCCAAGGAAAAGAUGAGGUUUUUCCCCUUCGAUUACCUUUUGAGGGAUGUUUAGGCUCAAAUUCUGCUUGCCACAGAGGAAACAUUUCUGCUGUAGUUGUUUACCUCCAUCCUAGCUGGCAGUGUGGGACACACACAUACAGCAAGUGAAGGUGGGGGUUUGGGCCUGUAUAGAGGUCAGCUACGCUGCAGGCUCAUCUAUUCACACCAGCAGGUACAGAGAAAACUAGUGUUUUGUAAAGUCAAAUAUUUGUUGGGGGUUGGAGUUCUGGGGUUGGAGGAGGGGCUGUUCUGGGCAUCAGUUGAGCAGAUGCCCAGGAUGCCUGGGGGAGACCAGCUUCCCCUACAAAUCAGAGCUCUAAAUUACAAGGUUUUUACCAACGUGAACAGUUGGGGGAAGUCGUCUGCUCUCAUUUGCGUAAUGGUUUCUGUCACUGGUGAUUAGACACAGGAUGAAGGAAAAGAAAUUUGACAAUUAGGAAUGAGCGAUCAUUAAUCUGAAUCUGUUAGGAGACAGAGAGGGGAAGGAUCCUUAUCAGUGGGCCAGCCCAGUAUGGGGAGACACUCCCUCCCUCUGCCCCCAGAGACUCCUGGGCUACAUCCUCUUUCAGUAUUGCCACAAGUGGGCAGAGCUUGUAUUUCUUAACAAAGAUUAGGGACCCAGUUGCCAGCCUGAGAUGGAUAUAGGAACAGACAUCUUUGGGCAUGAGCCAACAAAGAUAGAAAUAGAUGAGUGUCAGGUACAAGCUAUAAGGCAAAGAAUAACAGUGGAAAAGUUUUGACAUGUGUUUGCCAUUUGUGGAAAAUGUUUUUGUAAUAGUCAACACCCCUCAUAGCCCACCUGUGACAAGUACUUGUUACAUUCCAGCACUGUAGGGCGUGAGGAAAAUCUGGUCCUUAUCAAAUCCCAGGAGCUUCUGCUUAGUUGGGGAAGAAAUUACAUGAAGCAACCAGAGGUUAUAAGGCCACACUUGUAUAUCGUGCACCCUGUGUGGACAAGAUUAGGGACUGUUGAGAGAGGAGGAAACCAGUAGAGAGCAAAGCUCUACCCAGGCUCCUUGUAAGCCUCUGGGCUCCCCCGAGAGGGCCUCGCUACUCUACGCUUCCUAGCAACGUUGAUGUCCCCACAACCCCACAUCAGUGCAGCUGUGGCUGUGUGGAGGGGCUCUGAGGCCUCUGAGGCCAGAUGUGUAAACAGUGCUGAGGUUCAGUAAUAGGAUGAGUCUUCAGGUGUGGAGCAGCCCACCUUGGCUCUUCCCAUGUCUCUGUGUUACUUCUCAUAUUCUGCUGUCCUUUCAAACUUCAAGGACAGUAUUAAUUUAUACUAGUAUUUCUUCCUCAGUUUUGUGACUUGAAUGCAGUGAGUGCCUUAGAGGAUCCAAGGAUGAAGGAAUGCGGGUUGGUGGUUCUCUCUUUCAGAAUGGGAACUUCCCAAAAAUGGGGCUGCGUCUCGCCUCUCAGUAGGUUCCCUACCUCUGGGUCUUCCACCCUUCAAAAUCUGGUACAGAAUUUAGCAGGGGCUGCAGGGAAUGACCCUCAGGGACCAGUUUCACCCAGAUGGGGUAGAUGAUGAGGUAUACCUAGAAGUAGCUCAGGGCUCCAGAGUCUGGCCUUUCAGCUGGUGUCUUACUCCCCUUUGAGACCUUCAGCUGCUUGUCUUCCACUGCCUGCAUACUUCUCUGAUGUCUUCUCAAACUGUUGGCUCUAAAGGGAUGUUCCAGCCUCCCUCUCCAGAGCUGCCUGCAGUUUCCCUUAUUCAGCUGUCUCCUGCCUAGUCUCUCCAGCGGCCUCCUUACCAAGACCCUUUUUCCUAAACAGUUGUCCUUCCCUCAGAAACUCCAUGGCUGCAAGUGUGAAUAGACUUGUCUUUAGGAUCCCUCUCUCUGGUCAUCCCUGAUCAUCUUAGGGCCGUCUCCCUUUUCUGAUUUUUGACAGCUCUGUUUAUUUUGCCCAUGGCUAGUCCUCUUGUUUUGUGUCUGCUGUGUGUUCUUGCCCUUCCAUUGUCAGUUCUGUACAUCCUGGUUCAGCUUGUCUCACUGUGGUAGCCCCUUCUGCUUGUCUUCAGCCAUCUUGGUUUAAUCCUCAUAGGUCAUGGAUGAAUGGAGCCUUGCUGAGCACUUUGAGGGCAUUUCUGUUGGGCACAACCUCAGAAACGGGAAGUCUUGAGGCCUGGGGGCGUGUGGUCAGUGAGGCCUCCAGAGGUGGGUUAGGGGUGGGCACCUACAAGGGCCAGUUGAGGGGAGAGGUGCAGGGAUUGCUGAGGAGACUUUGUGAGAAUGAUGUCAGGCCCGGGAAGCUGGUGUGGAAGAACUGAGCUGUCAGAAGGAGAUACCAAUAUCCCCUUUGCAGGGUGGUGAUGGGCAUCAAACAUGACGUGGAACAUGUCCCCUUCAUGGAGGGUUUCCAUCUAAAUGCAUCUGUGUGCCUUAGGGAUCAGUAGUUCAGGGGUGGUGGACUUUUUUGAGUGUCUCCUAAUUUCUCUGAGGUGUCUUUGGCUCUGUGUCACCAAAUGUGCCUGACCUCUGCAUCCCAGUGGUUGCUGAAAGGGAAACAGUAUAUUGCGUAGUCAGAUGUCAGGAGUAGAGAUCUUAAUGAGAAAGGCCCUGGCAGCUGGAGAGAUGAGAGGACCUAGUGGUCAGCUUAUACCCAGACUAUCUCUCCACUCCUCCAAGAGUUUGAGUCCCAUAGCUGAUGAAAGAAUUUACAUAUGGGCUCCCCCCUGCUUUCCCACUGAAAAUCUAUUCUCAUAUUUUGGGAAGGAGCAUAUGUCCUUUAACUUUCAAUGGUAAACAAUCUAGGAUAGUGUUUAAAGGCAUGGAUUUUGGAGUCACAUAUAGUUGGUUUGAAUUUCUAGCUUCACUACUUACCAGCUGGGUUUGACCUUGGUUGAUUUACUUAACCUCUCUGAGCCUCAGUUUCCUCAACUAUAAUAACAUGGGUGGAGGGAGGCAUGUUGAAAAUAUCUACCUCAGGGUUGUUGGAAUAACUGAAACAAUGUUUGUAAAGCUUUAGCACAGUGCCUGGCAAGCACUUAAUAAAUGGCUGUGGUGGUGGUGGUUAUAUUUAUUAUGUGAUUUAUUCAGAAACUUGGUUUCAGUGAUCUCUAAACAGAUUUCCAGUGGUUCUUUCUCUCUCAAGAAAAGCAUAGGGAAAAACGAGAAACACCUUAGAUAAACCAUAUUGAGUUGAGGGUAGACAGAAGAGUCUAGUACCUAAACUCACCCUAGAGGAAGAGAAACAGGAAGUGUCUUAUGCCUCUUCUGCCUGGGCAGCCAGACUUUACUGCUGUACUACCAGCCCAGGGCCUUGGGUGAGAAGGUUUCAGGUCUGAGCUCCCCUUGCACUGUGUGAGAGGCCGUGGAGCCGAAUGAGUCCUUAUUAUACCUGGAGAAGCUGUUGUCUCCUCACACCAUGAAAUGUAAUAGCAGUCAAAUCAGGCCCCUCUUGAUUCAAUUUUAGUCCAUGCCUUUCCAUGUAUUUAAAUUAUAUAAGUGUUGGCCAGGUGUGGUGGCUCACACCUGUAAUCCCAGCACUUCGGGAGGCUGAGGCAGGAGGAUCACUUGAGCCCAGGAGUUCGAACCAACCUUGGGCAGCAUAGUGAGACCCCUUCUCUUAAUAAUUUUUUUUGAAAAUAAUUUUUUAAAAAUUACAAAUAUGGACCAGACACCUGGGAGGAUUACCUCACGCCUGUAAUCCCAGCACUUUGGGAGGCUGAGGUGGGUGGAUCACCUGAGGUCAGGAGUUUGAGACUAUCCUGGCCAACAUGGUGAAACCCUGUCUCUACUAAAAAUACAAAAAUUAGCCAGAUGUGGUGGUGGGUACCUGUAAUCCCAGCUACUCGGGAGGCUGAGACAGGAGAAUCACUUGAACCUGGGAGGCGGAGGUUGCAGUGAGCUGAGAUCACGUCAUUGCACUCCAGCCUGGGUGACUACAGUGAGACUCCCUCUCAAAAAAAAAAAAAAAAAAUUAUGAGUAUGUUAAGAUUGUUCUAGGGGAGAAGGGCAAUCAAAAUUCAGAAAAAUAUGAGUGGGAUGUUAAUAGCUACCAUUUGUUGAACACUUCUGUUCCAGGCACUGUAUUAGUUCGUCCCCAUGUGGUGCUCUCAGAUCAGUAGGGGAGACAGGCAGGCAGUUAGAAUUAUGGUGUAUAGAGGAGAAGCAUUGCACUAUGUCCAGUUUUUUAUGGUAGGCUUCCUGCAGAAAGUGAUAAGUCCAAGCUGAUAUGUGGAAGAUGAAUAAUUAACCAGAGGUUGGGGGAUUUCCCCCUUAGCUUCUCUUUCUUCCAGUCCAGCAGUCCAAAACAAACACUGCUUCCCAAUGCCUAAGGGUUUUGUCGUACCUUACUCCAGGGAAUGGGUGAGACAGUAGAUCCCAAGAAGAAAACCCUUUGGUUAGUCACAGAAAUCUGAAAGUCUUGGUUGCUGGCUCAGAUUUGUCCUGGAGUGGACGUAGAUUGGACUUGCUUAUUUGUAGCCCUCCACCGUUCUCAUUUGUGUUCUGGCCUCUGGAGCCACCCUGCCAGACCCUACUUGGAAGAAAUGUUGAAUCAAGCUACUCAGACUUCAGCCUGAGAUGUAUUAUGGCUGGCUGGAAUUCUCAGCCCUUUCCACAUCAUGAUCCCAUUAAUCUCUUGGGUCUAUCCCCACGCCCAGCCACCUCUCCUCCUCACUAUAAGCCAAGUCUCCCUGCAGUUCUCUAUAAAUACUCAGAUCCUCUUGCCUCAGACCCUGGUCCCUAGCUUUGUGGGUGAAGAAGAUACCUCUUUAGCUUGUGCCAACCCAUCCCUCUGGGCUACAGGCCAUUCUGUAGUCACCUUGCAGUCACGUCUUUCCUUCUAGAUAACUGGCUCUGGGCCUUGGAAACCUUCUCUUUGGCUCUAGCUAAUUUUGCUGUUUUAUUCCGUUUACUUAAAACCUAUUCACUUGGUCAUUGAGGUCAGAACUAUCAGGAAAGCUGUGCUCCUUAACCCAUCAUCUAAGCUAAGCUUGGGCCAGGUUUUUAUUACCUCUUGAAUAUAUAUAGUGCAAUAUAGUGUAGUGGUUGAGAGUGGAGUCUGCAUACCUGGAUCUGCCAUUCUGCAUGACUUUGGGCAAAUGGACAAACUGCCCGAAACUUGACUUGUUUAUAUGUAUGGGGAAGACAUCAUUUACAUUGUCAGGGUAAGGCUUAGCAGAAUGACCGGUCCAUAGCAAGGGCUCAGUCUUUCUGUGUCUCUCAGUCUUUACCUCUCUUCCCCAUCUAGCUUUCUGUCUAAGUUCCUGUUUCUAGUCUCAGGGCAUAUCUAGUUGUCAGCUCCUGAGCAGAGCAGAGGUAUAAGUGUCAACUCAUGCUUGUGUUACCAGUUCCUACCCCUGUCAGUAACCUCUGAUGCUUACAAGGAUACUAUCACCUAUGCCAUCAGUGGGGAAUGACCUUCCAAAAAUAUUUUUAACAAUACUAAAAAUACCUGAAACAUACUGGGUGAAAAUAAGACAUUGGAGCUGCUGCUCCCCAAGGAGAUAAAAGGACAGUUCCUAAAGAGGCAUUGAAGGUUUGUAUGAGCCAGCAGCACAGUCAGAAGGCAAGAAGGAGACCCUGGGAUGUGCACAAGGAUGCAGGAGACGAGAUUGUCACAGAGGCUGUCAUGCUAGUAAGAGUCAGAGGUUACUGAUGGGUAGAGAUUGUCAGAGUCUGCCUUGCUAGUCUAGAGGUAGGACCAUGGAUUUAAGAACGUUGCCUCCAAGUUUUUGAAUUGUGAAUUUUUGAUCAUAUUUGAACAAAACCCCACCUACAGUCUGCAUGGUCAUUGUUCUCACAAGGGUUUGUGUGAUGCACUGACAAGAACAGAGGCUUUGGAGGUGACUCCUGGGUUUGAAUCACCAUUUGCCACUAGCUAAUUCUAACCUUAGGUAAGUCAGUGUCUCUGGGUCUCAACCUCUUCCUCUGUGAGGGGUAGGAAAUAGCACAUAACUUGUAGCAUUGUUAUAAGGGCUCGUGAUAAUGUUUUUAAAACACCUGGCUCAAGCACUCAGGAAAAUGUUUUAUUAUGAAGACCAAGUGUCUCUGAAAAGUGUUUCCUUAGUGUCUGGAGAGACUACAGCAGCAAGGCUUUUCUGAUCCUACUCUGACUCUCAAGAUAAUGGUGCUUGAAGUGAAAUCACAGAAGAGAUGACUGGGGCAGGAAAAGCAAGAUGGAAAAGAUAAAGUUGUGGAAGGGACUGAAAGUCCAUGAAGUGCUGGGCUGGGGACAGAAAGGGUUUAAUAGGGCAGGGUCUUGAGGAACAGGAACAGAGACCUUGGUUCUGGGUUGCCAUCUGAUUCCCAGAAGAGUAAAGGAAAUGGGGCAGGAGGAUGUCUGUGGAGGACACAGUGUGGCUGAGUGGAGAGAACACAAGCUUCUGGCCAGUGAACCUAAGUGAGAAUGUCAGUGGACUUUGCACAGGCUGGGUGCCUUUGGGGGUGUUCAUCUCGCUAUGCUUCGGUCCCCUCAUUUAAAAAAAUUGGUUAAUAAUAUGAUGACCUGCCAAUGUGUGUGGAAAUACUAUGUAAACUGAGCACUAUAUAAAUGCUGGUUGUUGAGAUAUUGGGAGUGGGGGUUUCGGGAGAUUUUGUUUGUUUGUUUUUUUGAGAUGGAGUUUUCGCUCUUGUUGCCCAGGCUGGAGUGCAGUGGCGUGAUCUUGGCUCACUGCAACCUCCACCUCCUCCAGGUUCAAGCAAUUCUGCCUCAGCCUCCCGAGUAGCUGGGACUCAGGCGUGCGCCACCAUGCCUGGCUAAUUUUGUAUUUUUAGUAGAGAUGGGGUUUCUCCAUGUUGGUCAGGCUGGUCUCGAACUCCCGACCUCAGGUGAUCUGCCUGCCUUGGCCUCCCAAAGUGCUGGGAUUACAGGUGCGAGCUACCACACCUGGCCCUGGAUUUCUUAAUAGGUCCUCUUAUGUGGCUAUUGAGAAUGAAUGAGACAACUCAUUAACUAACUAAGUUAAUUCAGAACUUAGUGCCUAGUAAGUGCUCAGUAAAUGUUAGUUUCUUUUCCUCCAUUUCUUCUUAGGAAGCAUCGUUUACCCAGCAUAAACAGGAGGACUCAACUGUGCAUGUCUUAGUGUGAACAAGUAACAUCAGAUUUCCCUUUUCUGAGGAGAGAUCAGUUCUGUAAGAGGGAGCAUGAGUGUGAAUGGGGAAGAAUCAUGGAGAAGGGAGCAGGACUCCACAGUACUGGAGAUGGAGUAGGGACCUCUGGGAAUCGUUGGCAUGGGGGUGUGGUGCAGAAAGGGUGAUGCUAAGAGGUGAGAGUCUCAAGAAAGAAGAUGGGUGUUCUAGAGGGGAAAGCUAAACGAUGAUAGGCAAUGAGGAGCGGAGGACAAGACCCUGAACUAAGGGUGAGGAGGCCAGCAUUCUGUCAGGAGAACCUUAGGAAUUGUGACCAGAAGUCAAAGUUGUUACAGCAAUCCUGCAUUCAACCAGGUUUCAUCUGAAAAACUUAAGAGUUGCUAGGCACAGUCGUGCACACUUGUAAUCCCAACACUUUGGGAGGCUUGAGUCAGGAGGAAGCUUGAGGCCAGGAGUUUGAGAUCAGCCUAGGCAGCAUAGUGACACCCCAUCUCUUGAAAAAACAAACACUCUUAAGAGCAGUGGUUCACCUAGAAAUAAAAAGCAGAAAUCAUCAAGAUGAGAAGACAUUUUGUGUUUUGACAGCCAAGGAAAUUUGCCACUGAGACAAGGUAUCUGACAGCCUAGAUGGGAUUCUAGACUUCUGUGAGAAAGUGCAGUUAGGCCCUGAAUAGCGUCAAACUCAGGGAUGUGAGCUGACUGACUGCCUUUUUAUGUAAUGGAGGCCAUGUGAUAGGGCUUUAUGAGGCCACAAAUAGCACUUUCUGGGUCCUUUCACAGUCUAGUCAGUGGCCCAACCAACAUAUCUGGUUGUUCUGCAAUCUCAGUCAUCUGAGAAGAUAACCUCCAAAAUACAUGCAGUGGCAUCAGGUGUUUCCUUGGUAGGUGUGCAUCUUUUAAUGAUGGAGGACUUAGGAUGAAGAACAGGUGUGUUUAAAAACAUCAAACCCCCACAUCAUUACUAUUUGCUGUAAGGAUCUAUGCAGUUUGUAUUUUAAGUCCUUGACAUAUGGAAGAGCAUUUGUGAGAGUAACAGGUUUGCUUUGUAAUGCCAACUAAAAAGUGUGUAUUUAUACUCGAAUUUUAAGUUGAAAUUUUGCUAAGUUUCUUUUUUUUUUUUUUGAGACGGAGUCUCACUCUGUUGCCCAGGCUGGAGUACAGUGGUACAAUCAUUGCUAAGUCUUUCUGUAGUUUUAGAACAUUUAGAACAACUUAAGAUUUCCUGUAUUUAUAAACUUAAUUUAUUGGAAAUAUAAGUACUUGAUCAGGUUUUGUCUUGGUCAGAUAAAUUAAGUACUUAAGGAAAUCAAAUACAUUAAUCAUAUAAAUGCCAUUUAAGUGUUUAAAGGAGUUUAGUUAAAUGUAAGUUGGAUCAAACAUUAAACUUUUUUGUUUUAUAAGCAAAAUAAUAAGAUUUGUUAGCAGAACUUAAAAGCUUAGAAAAGAGAGGAUUUUGGAUAUGUAACUUUGAAGAGGUGAAUAGUUUGCUCUUUUCUGAGACAGGGCAUUGCUUUUCGACGCAGGCUGGAGUGCAGUGGGGCAAGCAUGGCUCACUGCAGCCUCAACCUCCUGGACUCAAGUGAUCCUCCUGCCUCAGCCUCCCAUGUAGCUGGGAUCACAGGCACAUGCCACCACACCUGGCUAAUUUUUUAUUUUUUGUAGAGACAGGGGCCUCACUUCAUUGCCCAGGCGGAUCUCGAACACCUGGGCUCAAGCAGUCCUGCCUCAGCCUCCCAAAGUUCUGGGAUUACAGGCAUAAGCCACUGUGCCUGGCCUUGAAUAUAUUUUUUAACCAAAGUAAUUUAUGAAUAUAAAUUGUUUCUAUAUAACCCAAAGUCACUCUCAUUGACAUUAAGAAACUCAGAGAGUGGGUUCUAAAUGUAAUAUUACCACACACCCAAGUCACUUAGCCUCUACAAGUACCACGUAACUAGCAGCCGUUAAAAGAUGGCCACCGCUAGUCCAGUCGGCCACAGACAUGGUUUUGUUUGGCCAAUACAAGUUUUUGAAAGUUUUAAAAAAUUGACAACAUUAAAGAUCAGAAACUUGACCUAAAAA